UCCGAGCAAUGACCCUGGUAUCUAGGUGAAAUCACAACCCUGUUUUUAUAUAUAAGAAGUCCUUGCUUAAAGUCAAUAGCAUCUUGGAAACUGCAACCUUAAGGAAAUGAUAUACAGCAGGUCCUCAAGUAAAAUUGUUUUGUUCAAAGUCCAUUAGUUAUAUUGUUGAUAAGGAAAAACACACGGUUUCAUUAUAAAUCAUUUCACUUAAAUCACAGUUUCCAAAAACAUAUUGAGGGUGUUAAUUGAGGACUUACUGUAUUUCAAAUUUAAGUUAAUUUUCACAGUUCGUGUGGAAAUUAUUUACAUAUUACAUCUGUAAAAUCACUUUAAGCAGGCUAUGUGUGACGAACUUGUUCACGAGCCCUCAACCUUGGCUUUUAUUGACCUCACCUGGGGAGCUUACAAAUGAUGAUGGCUGGGCUCUCUUACCCAGAGAUUUUGAUUUACUUGAACCUGUGUGGGUCUGAGAGGUUUUAAAAGCACCAGUGAUAGUUCAGACGAUGAAGUUCUUCAAGGGAUCAAGCUCAAAUGGAGGACAAGAAAAAACUAUACUAAGGUUCCUGGUAGGUUUCCUGAAUCCAAUCACCUCUUCCUGAAUGACUCACUGAAGAUCUGUCCUACGCAAGGUGUCCGAGCUACACAGAGCCACAGAAUCUCACAGGUGUCUCAGAAUUCCUCCUCCUGGGACUCUCAGAGGAUCCAGAACUGCAGCCGGUCCUCGCUGGGCUGUUCCUGUCCAUGUACCUGGUCACGGUGCUGGGGAACCUGCUCAUCAUCCUGGCUGUCAGCUCUGACUCCCACCUCCACACCCCCAUGUACUUCUUCCUCUCCAACCUGUCCUUGGCUGACAUCGGUUUCACCUCCACCACGGUCCCCAAGAUGAUUGUGGACAUGCAAACUCACAGCAGAGUCAUCUCCUAUGAAGGCUGCCUGACUCAGAUGUCUUUUUUUGUCCUUUUUGCAUGUAUGGAUGACAUGCUCCUGAGUGUGAUGGCCUAUGACCGGUUUGUGGCCAUCUGUCACCCCCUGCACUACCGAAUCAUCAUGAACCCACGCCUCUGUGGCUUCUUAAUCUUGUUGUCUUUUUUUAUUAGUCUUUUGGACUCCCAGUUGCACAAUUUGAUUAUGUUACAGCUCACCUGCUUCAAGGAUGUGGACAUUUCUAAUUUCUUCUGUGACCCUUCUCAACUCCUCCACCUUAGGUGUUCCGACACCUUCAUCAAUGAAAUGGUCAUAUAUUUCAUGGGUGCCAUAUUUGGCUGUCUCCCUAUCUCAGGGAUCCUUUUCUCUUACUAUAAAAUUGUUUCCCCCAUUCUGAGAGUUCCAACAUCAGAUGGGAAGUAUAAAGCCUUCUCCACCUGUGGCUCUCACCUGGCAGUUGUUUGCUUAUUUUAUGGAACAGGGCUUGUAGGGUACCUCAGUUCAGCUGUGUUACCAUCCCCCAGGAAGAGUAUGGUGGCUUCAGUGAUGUACACUGUGGUCACCCCCAUGCUGAACCCCUUCAUCUACAGCCUGAGGAACAAGGACAUUCAAAGUGCCCUGUGCAGGCUGCAUGGCAGAAUCAUCAAAUCUCAUCAUCUCCAUCCUUUUUGUUAUAUGGGAUAGAAAUGGCAGCAAAAUUUAACACCUAGGCCUGCAAAUUCUGCCUCCUUGGUCACAUUAUUUUGGUUGCUUGAUGGCUUUCAUUCCUCUCUGGGUUUCGUAUGUGAAUAUUGCUUGCUUUGUUUUGUCUUUAAUUGCAAUGGGUGAGUAUUCUGGUAUCCUUUGUUCAUCAUACACAUCAUGAAUGAUUCCAAUAUACCUAGACAGCCUCCUUUAGUAUCUGUGCAAUGACCUUGAUAUCCAGGUGCAAUCACAAUCUUUUCUGAUAGACUUGAAAUCCUCACUUAACUUUGUCAAGAGGUUUUUGGAAACUGCAACUUUAAAAAAAAAGCGCAGCAGGUCCUGAAAUAAGUUCAUUUUGUUCAAUGUUGUUUAGUUUUAAUUUUGGUGAGAAAUGAAUAAAUUGGUUUCAUGGUU